GGAACACCUCGGGUCACCCCCGACAACGGUGGUGGGAGGGAGAGCGGCCUCCUCCUCCCUGGUGGGGCCUGUCUGGGUGAAGCCCCUCUGUUCCCGAGGAUCGUCUGCCUUAUUGAAACCAUCUAAUUGGAGAUCCGCAGAUUAGGCUACCAAGACACAGCUGCCUCCAGCAGAAUUUGUGUAGUGGACACUUGUACGUGCACUUUGGAGACAGCAAGCAUGAGGCCUGCAGCUGACAGCUUUGAGUGGCUGUGAACCUGACUAUGGAAAAGAUGUGACUCCCCACCCCCAGCCGGGUGCUCCGAGCCAUGGCCGACACCAUCUUCGGCAGCGGGAAUGAUCAGUGGGUUUGCCCCAAUGACCGGCAGCUUGCCCUUCGAGCCAAGCUGCAGACGGGCUGGUCCGUGCACACCUACCAGACGGAGAAGCAGAGGAGGAAGCAGCACCUCAGCCCGGCGGAGGUGGAGGCCAUCCUGCAGGUCAUCCAGAGGGCAGAGCGGCUCGACGUCCUGGAGCAGCAGAGAAUCGGGCGGCUGGUGGAGCGGCUGGAGACCAUGAGGCGGAAUGUGAUGGGGAACGGCCUGUCCCAGUGUCUGCUCUGCGGGGAGGUGCUGGGCUUCCUGGGCAGCUCGUCGGUGUUCUGCAAAGACUGCAGGAAGAAAGUCUGCACCAAAUGUGGGAUCGAGGCCUCCCCUGGCCAGAAGCGGCCCCUGUGGCUGUGUAAGAUCUGCAGUGAGCAAAGAGAGGUCUGGAAGAGGUCGGGGGCCUGGUUCUACAAAGGGCUCCCCAAGUAUAUCUUGCCCCUGAAGACCCCUGGCCGAGCUGAUGACCCCCACUUCCGACCUUUGCCCACGGAACCGGCAGAGCGAGAGCCCAGAAGCUCUGAGACCAGCCGCAUCUACACGUGGGCCCGAGGAAGAGUGGUUUCCAGUGACAGUGACAGUGACUCGGAUCUUAGCUCCUCCAGCCUAGAGGACAGACUCCCAUCCACUGGGGUCAGGGACCGGAAAGGCGACAAACCCUGGAAGGAGUCAGGUGGCAGCGUGGAGGCCCCCAGGAUGGGGUUCACCCACCCGCCGGGCCACCUCUCUGGGUGCCAGAGCAGCCUGGCCAGUGGUGAGACGGGGACAGGCUCUGCUGACCCGCCAGGGGGACCCCGCCCCGGGCUGACCCGAAGGGCCCCGGUAAAAGACACACCUGGACGAGCCCCCGCUGCUGACGCAGCUCCAGCAGGCCCCUCCAGCUGCCUGGGCUGAGGUGUCUGGUGCCUGGAACAGACUUCCCUGUGGAGGAUUCCUGCCAGACCCUGCCCGGCUCCUCCCUGACCGGUCCUUGUGCCCUCACCAGACACCCUGUUGGCCAUGACUCAACAAACCAGUGUUGGGAGCCGUCUGCCUCCCCAGCUCAGUGCCUUUCUGCACCCCUUCUCUCCUGGGGAGCUGUCUGCAUCCGCCACCCCCUCCAACCACUGCCCUCAGCCCCCGACCUUAUUUAUUACCCUCCCCUCCCACACCCCCAAUCUACCUGGUGAUGAUUUUAAGUUUGCGCGUGUCUUGGGUUGGGCUGGGGGGUUUCCCACAUGCAGUGUCAGAGGGGCCGCCCGGUGGGGCUAUCUCCGUUGCUAUAUUAAUGGCAAGACUAAAUGAAACCUAGGGCACGGCCUCCGAAGCUGCGUGUGGCCCCUUAGAGGUGAGCAUCAGAGCCAGAGCAGUGAGGGGGAGACUCACCCACCCUCUCCCUCUCCCUUCAGCUCUGGGAGGCAGGCGCAGUGCCCCCCUCCCAUGGGCUGGCCCAGGACCGUGGGUGAAACCUGGGUCUGUUUAGUUUCUUUGGUUUUUGUAUGUUUGUUUGUUUUUGACACAGUCUCGCUUUGUUGCCCAGGCUGGGGUGCAGUGGCACGAUCGCGGCUCACUGCAACCUCCACCUCCCGGGCUCAAGCGAUUCUCUCACCUCAGCCUCCUGAGUAGGUGGGAUUACAGAUGCCCGCCACCACACCCAGUUAAUUUUUGUAUUUUUAGAAGAGAUGGGGUUUCUCCAUGUUGGCCAGGCUGGUCUUGAACUCCUGGUCUCAAGUGAUCUGCCCGCCUCGGCCUCCCAAAGUGCUGGGAUUACAGGUGUGAGCCACCGCACCCAAUCCUAUUAGGUUUCUUUGAAUCCCCUCAUGGCCUGCCUGGUUUUUGCUCAGCCUGUCUUCAGCUUGAGGAGCUGGGAAGCUCUGGUGGAUGCUAUGAACUCACUUGCUGAAGAGCAGCGUUCAGGUGCAUCCCCAGCCAGGGCACGUGGCUCCCUCAGCCAUGAAUUCACUUCUCUUCAGGAGGUUUGGCUUGGCAUGAAAAUACUUCAUUCAGAGUAUGGGCAAAUGCUUCUGGAAAACCCUUCCCUGAAGAGAGAGAACGUGUGUGUGUGUGUCGGUGAUCACACCCUCCCAUCCUUCCUGCCUCCUGCCCCAAACCCCGGGUUCCUGGGUCUGGAAGGGCCUUCUCUCCAAGCUGGGAGCUCCUGGGCCCCCACCAUUCACUUUUUGUCCUUGCUGCUGGCAAACAGUAAAGAAACUCACUUUCCCUGUGGCACGUUAUGCUUCAGAAUUAAAACAAUGAAGAUUAAAAUUUGCACCGAGCCAGUGUGUUGAUCGAAGACCACGAUUGCCUGUGUUUCUGAGAUGCGUCCAUGGAAAAAUGGAAAAAACUGUGGUGCGUUGACUUGCUGGAACCCUUCCUAA